AUUUGAACUCCGUCGCUUGCUGUCUCGCUGUCCCCUCUCUGCCCCGCGCACCUCGCUCCCCCUCCCGGCCGGCGCUCGCAGUGGCGCGCCUGCUCGCUCUCCCGCUAAGCGACGAGUCUUCAACAAGUUGGAGGAAGGCAGGAACGCAGGGGUUAAGCUCGGAAAGCCGCAAUUACCAAGAUCGUGACCCUCCCACACAGUACAGUAACUUAUAUACUUACCUGGAAGAACCCGCUUUGCCGCCGGGCAAACACCCGUGGGGGGCGGGGAGGGGCCGGAGGGAGCGGGCCGGCAGGAGAGGGGCUGCUUCCAGCUGGCUGCAGUGCGGACGGGACCGGCGCGCUCCCGUGGCCCCCAGACCGAGGUGGUCAAACCUGUCCUGACACCCAGAGGUCUGCAUGAGGGGUGGCCACUGAAGGAGGAGUUCUCAAAGGCCACAGGUGAUGAAGAGCUUGGAUGAAUAAACUUAGAAGUCCCAGGAAAAUAGCAAAAAUUUCAUCUCCUGAAGAAAUUUGAAGAUUUUUUUGGAUAUUCUUUUAAAGGUGAAACUUUUCUUCUUUAGUUGUCACAGGUAGUACUGAUGGAAUUGGAAAAUCAUAUGCAGAAGAGUUAGCAAAGCAUGGAAUGAAGGUUGUCCUUAUCAGCAGAUCAAAGGAUAAACUUGACCAGGUUUCCAGUGAAAUAAAAGAAAAAUUCAAAGUGGAGACAAGAACCAUUGCUGUUGACUUUGCAUCAGAAGAUAUUUAUGAUAAAAUUAAAACAGGCUUGGCUGGUCUUGAAAUCGGCAUCUUAGUGAACAACGUGGGAAUGUCGUAUGAGUAUCCUGAAUACUUUUUGGAUGUUCCUGACUUGGACAAUGUGAUCAAGAAAAUGAUAAAUAUUAAUAUUCUUUCUGUUUGUAAGAUGACACAAUUGGUACUGCCUGGCAUGGUGGAAAGAUCCAAAGGGGCUAUUCUGAACAUUUCAUCUGGCAGUGGCAUGCUCCCUGUCCCACUCUUGACCAUCUAUUCUGCAACCAAGACUUUUGUAGAUUUCUUCUCUCAGUGCCUCCAUGAGGAGUAUAGGAGCAAGGGCGUCUUUGUGCAGAGUGUCCUGCCAUACUUCGUAGCUACAAAACUGGCUAAAAUCCGGAAGCCAACUUUGGAUAAGCCCUCUCCGGAGACGUUUGUGAAGUCUGCAAUUAAAACAGUCGGCCUGCAAUCCCGAACCAAUGGAUACCUGAUCCAUGCUCUUAUGGGCUCGAUAAUCUCAAACCUGCCUUCUUGGAUUUAUUUGAAAAUAGUCAUGAAUAUGAACAAGUCUACACGGGCUCACUAUCUGAAGAAAACCAAGAAGAACUAAGCAUUGAUAACUGCAUUGUAACUUGGCCAGAUGCUCCAGCAUAUGCACGUUCACUGCAAAGCACCCUACUGGUUUUGAAAAUCUGACCUUGUCAUUUCAAUAGUUAUUAACAUGACUAAAUAUUAUCUUAAUUAAGAGGAAAAUAGAAGUUGCUUUUAGGGGUUUCUGACAUAUAUUCUGGAUACUAUCCGAGGUAAUUUUGAAGUUUAAUAUAAAUGCUCAUAUCAAAUGAAUAUAGAACUAAUAUUGUCGGGAACACCUAAUAGAAAGGAAUACUAUUAUAGCAAAUCACAGAAUGAUAGACUCAAGCAUAAAACUUGGCAGUUUUAUCUGCUUCAAAAUGCCAUUGAUCAUUAUUCCUGUAUUUUCUCUGAAACUGAUUAUAAAAACCAAUGUCCAGCUACUCUUUUGUUUUUGACACUUGAAGAAAUGGAGAUCGAUUUGAUUUGUUUAUAAGCAGACACACUGCAAUUUACAAAGAUCUCUUUACGGUUUUAUAAAAUUAUCUUCCAGUUUGUACAUUUAUAUGGAAUUGUUCUUUAUCAAGGGUAGCUAAUGACAUGAAAAUAAUUGUGAAAUAUGGAAUUAUUUCUGACACAUGAAGCCCACUAAACUAUGCUUUCUUAUAAUGCAUAUUUCUUCUCAGUUUAAAUGUAUGUAAAUAUCGAAGCUAUAUGGUAUGAUUUAUAAAGAUAAAUGGGCCAAAGUGUACAUUGAGACUGGCAGCCAUCUAUGGUACCACUGAAACCCUGACCCAGAAAAGUGGCUUGCUUGGACACCCAGCUGCCUUUGUUUCUGCAUUAAACCAAUAUUGAUCACACAUAUGACACAGGCUAGUCCUAUAAAAGUAAUGACUUCAUAGAAAUGGCAUUAUAAUUUUUAAGUUGAUACUCUACAGGUAGCUAUUGAUAUAAUUAGUUUUAAUAAAACAUGCUGCAACCAUGGUAUACAACAAAAAUACAUUUCUUUGGUGAUUGAAAUUAAGGCCGUAUUUACAAUGACUUAAUAUAAGACUGACUUUUAUCCUGCUUCAUAACUUGUAUGGAGAACUCACCAAGAAAGAAUUCAAUACUGUGAAAUAUGCAGCAAGAAGAUUGGUCUUUACCUAGGCUGUGUUUCCUAAGCUCUGAGUUUUCAGCACCAGUAGAUUUGUAUUAAAAGAAAAAAAAAUGGGGCCUUAGCUUCUGGCUUUUAAUUUUGCCAGCUAAGGACAUAAAACAAAAAUAAACAAACAAAAACAAAUAGCCAUCUGCUAUCAGCAUCAUUAUGUAAAAGAAAAUAUAUUUUAGCCCCUAAAAUUAGGAAGAAUGUAAUCUCAGAAUAAAGGUUGUCAUUUAAGUUGAAUAAAUAUAUAGCUUUAUGAAAAA